AUUGCAGCCUCGGCGUUUGUAGAAGAGGAGCAUCUGCUCCAGGUGGGUUUGGAUUUCUGUCGGUUUUGCACAAGGGAUCCUAAAGGCGAUUGAAAUGGUACUUAGAGAAAGAAAGGAUCGGGGCCGGGGCUGUUCAUUUUGGGCCGCGCAAGCGUGGCUGAGUGUUCGGCGAGAGCGUGAACUGGGCGGCGAUGAGGUGGCGGCGCGGCUGUCACUUAAGUUGAAUAGGGCGGUGCCUUGUGGGGCCUCUGGGUGGACCGCCUCAGGUGCGCCGUGAAUGCCUUAGACCCCCCCGAAUACCUUCCCAGGGAAAUCUCUAGCCUGUCUCAUCUUAUUGCUUCUCUUACCCCGUGCAGUCAGGAUUUACUGUGCUCCCAUGGGGCGAGGAGCGGGGCCUAGUAAGAAGUUUCAGGCUGUAGGCAGGGGAAAGCAUAGCUGUUCCUUGCCUUCAGAGAGCAAAGGAGAUAAGCGAAACUGGAGGGGGAAAUGGGCUGUGUGACAUGUUCAGUUAGUUGACGUAGGUUCAGAAUAUCAUUGUUUUGCUGCAGAAUAAAAACCGGUCUCUUUUGACUGUUGAAUUCCUUUGGAGAGUUCUGGAAGAAGCAGAUUUCUGUCCCAAAGCCAAAUUCCAAUUUCUGUAUCUAGUUUCGGGUAUAUAAUUUGCACAUCACACUAGUAGUUUUAAUAUUCUGACAGUUAAAAGAGGAGUUAUACUACUUACUUAAGUCAACUGAAUACUAAUAUCUGGCAGGUUUUUUUUUGCCUAAGAUAAUUGUAGUAAGGAACAGAUUUGUUUAUUUAAUACUCACAUGGCACUUAGGUGCUGAGCGUUAUACUAAGCAUUUACUGAGCAUCUGCUGCGUGCCACGUACUUUUAUAUGGAAUAUUUUCUAUAAUCCUCACUUUCACCAUAUUGCAGAUAGGAAAACAGGCUUAGAGAGGUUAAAUGACUGGCCUGAGUUUACACAGGGAGCCAGUCAGAGCACGACUGAAAAUUGAAGAGUCUGUGCCGUAACUCACUAAAUGCUCUGUCUGCAGUUAGUUUAUCUGUUAGUGUAGCAGAAUUGUUACUCAAGCAGCAUGAUAAAGAUCUGCGGGAGCAUGCAAAAACGUAAACAGUGUUGGGCGCGGUGGCUCACGCCUGUAAUCCCAGCACUUUGGGAAGCCGAGACGGGCGGAUCACCGAAGGUUAGGGGUUCGAGACCAGCCUGGCCAGCAUGGUGAAACCCCGUCUCUACGAAAAAUACGCAAAAUACUGGGCGUGGUGGCGGGCGCCUGUAAUCCCAGCUACUAGGGAGGCUGAGGCAGGAGAAUCACUUGAACCCAGGAGGUGGAGGUUGCAGUGAGCUGAGAUCGCACCUUUGCACUCCGCCUGGGCAACAAGAGCAAAACUCCAUCUCAAAAAAAAAACAAAAACAAAAAAACCCCUAAACAAUAGUCUCAGUUUACAUGAGUUUAGAUUUCAGGGAAGCAAAACCAAGCAUACAUGAAAUAAUAAUACAGCACGGAAGGUAAUACAAGUGGGCUCUCUCAUAAAAACAAAUUUGUUUUGAGUUAAUUUGGAAUGUAGAACGUAUUUUCUACCAUAGUGACAAUAUUGACUGACAUUUAAAUUCAUAAAAGUUAUAUUUAAUUUUGUGUCUGAUUCCAUAAACUGUGCUUACUCUCUACAGCCUUGUUUCCACAGGACAUGUACUCUGAUGACAGGCUUACAAGAAUACAUCUUUUUCUUCUUUCUCCCCUUGGCAGUGUCAAUAGGAGCAGGUGCUGCAGUGAUUUGGAGCAAGACAGAUAUUUUAGAGCCUUAGAGACGUUGUGCUGGAAGAAUCUAAGAGGCUUCUAGUCCUACUUCCCAUCUGACAUUCAGUUUAUCCUAAAACAUUCCUGCUGAGUGGAUUGUCCAGCCUGUGCUUUUUCAUCUCCAGUGAUGGGAAACACUUCCAUUGAGUACCUCAUUCCACAUUUAUAUAGAUGGAAAAUGGGUAAGGAACAAUCAAAUUCAAUUCGGGAAGAAUAUAGAGGUGGUAAUAAUUGGUAAAAGUCUGCAGGGUUUUUUUUAACCAAAGGAAACUGGUUUGAGAAAAUUGUGAAAUCAGCAUUGAAAUUUGUUACCUACUCCAAUCAAGAUUUGCAAACUACAAAAAAAUCAUUCUGAAGCUUUCACCUAUAAAUAUAUACCAAGAUAAUUUCAGAUAAGAAUGUCCAGCAAGGAAGUGAAGACUGCUCUAAAAAGUGCUAGAGAUGCAAUCAGAAACAAAGAAUACAAAGAAGCUUUGAAACACUGUAAGACAGUGUUAAAGCAAGAGAAAAAUAACUAUAAUGCCUGGGUUUUUAUUGGCGUUGCUGCAGCUGAACUAGAACAACCUGAUCAGGCCCAGAGUGCCUAUAAAAAAGCUGCUGAAUUAGAGCCAGACCAAUUACUAGCUUGGCAGGGGUUAGCAAACUUGUAUGAGAAAUAUAAUCACAUAAAUGCUAAGGAUGACUUGCCUGGUGUUUACCAAAAGCUCCUGGAUCUUUAUGAGAGUGUUGACAAGCAGAAGUGGUGUGAUGUCUGCAAGAAACUUGUGGAUCUAUAUUACCAAGAAAAGAAACACCUAGAGGUGGCUCGAACAUGGCACAAGUUGAUAAAAACACGGCAGGAACAAGGUGCAGAAAAUGAAGAGCUUCAUCAACUAUGGAGAAAAUUGACUCAGUUCCUGGCUGAAAGUACAGAGGACCAGAAUAAUGAAACUCAGCAAUUGCUUUUUACUGCUUUUGAGAAUGCACUGGGAUUAUCAGAUAAGAUUCCUAGUGAAGAUCACCAAGUACUUUAUAGGCAUUUCAUUCAGAGUUUAUCCAAAUUUCCUCAUGAGUCUGCUAGAUUGAAGAAGGCCUGUGAAGGAAUGAUAAACAUCUAUCCUACUGUACAGUAUCCAUUAGAAGUGCUUUGUUUGCAUUUAAUUGAAUCAGGAAAUCUUACUGAUGAGGGGCAGCAGUAUUGUUGUAGAUUAGUGGAAAUGGAUUCAAAAAGUGGUCCAGGCCUCAUUGGCUUAGGCAUUAAAGCAUUACAAGACAAAAAGUAUGAAGAUGCUGUUAGGAACCUAACAGAAGGGUUAAAGGAAAGCCCUGUCUGCACAAGUGGAUGGUAUCAUCUGGCAGAAGCCCAAGUCAAAAUGCAUAGACCUAAAGAAGCUGUUCUUUCAUGCAGUCAAGCUCUGAAGAUCGUAGAUAAUCUUGGUGCGUCUGGUAACAGUCUUUAUCAGAGGAAUCUUUGUCUUCAUUUGAAAGCAGAGGCUUUGAUUAAACUCUCAGAUUAUGACUCUUCAGAGGAAGCAAUUCGUACGCUUGAUCAGAUUUCUGAUGCAGAUAAUAUCCCAGGACUUUUGGUUCUCAAAAGCUUGGCCUAUCGGAACAAAGGUUCAUUUGAUGAAGCUGCAAAGAUUAUGGAAGACCUUCUCUCUUCUUACCCUGACCUAGCUGAAGUUCAUGCCCUUGAGGCUUUGAUUCAUUUCACCAAAAAGGACUAUCUACAAGCAGAAAAAUGUUUUCAGAGAGCUCUUGAGAAAGAUACCGAAGUUGCAGAAUAUCAUUACCAACUUGGAUUAACAUACUGGUUCAUGGGUGAAGAGACAAGAAAAGAUAAAACAAAGGCUCUUACCCACUUUCUGAAGGCUGCAAGACUGGAUACAUAUAUGGGCAAAGUUUUCUGCUAUUUAGGUCAUUAUUAUAGAGACGUAGUGGGAGAUAAAAACAGAGCUCGUGGAUGUUAUAGGAAAGCCUUUGAAUUAGAUGACACUGAUGCUGAAUCUGGAGCUGCAGCAGUUGACCUAAGUGUGGAGCUUGAAGAUAUGGAAAUGGCUUUAGCUAUCCUAACAACAGUAACUCAAAAGGCAAGUGCUGGAACGGCAAAAUGGGCCUGGCUUAGGCGAGGACUAUACUAUUUGAAAGCUGGUCAGCAUUCUCAAGCAGUGGCUGAUUUACAGGCAGCAUUAAGAGCAGACCCAAAGGACUUCAAUUGUUGGGAAUCGUUAGGAGAAGCAUACUUAAGCAGAGGAGGCUACACAACAGCCUUGAAGUCCUUCACAAAAGCCAGUGAGCUGAACCCAGAAUCCAUAUACAGUGUGUUUAAGGUUGCAGCAAUACAGCAAAUCCUAGGCAAAUAUAAGGAGGCUGUAGCUCAAUACCAGAUGAUCAUUAAAAAGAAAGAAGAUUAUGUGCCUGCUUUAAAAGGUUUGGGUGAAUGCCAUCUUAUGAUGGCAAAAGCAGCUCUAGUUGAUUAUCUUGAUGGAAAAGCCGUAGACUACAUAGAAAAAGCACUGGAAUAUUUUACUUGUGCUCUACAGCAUCGAGCUGAUGUGUCCUGCCUCUGGAAGCUAGCUGGGGAUGCUUGUACCUGUCUGUAUGCUGUCGCACCAUCUAAAGUGAAUGUUCAUGUUUUAGGAGUCCUUCUAGGUCAGAAAGAAGGAAAACAAGUAUUAAAGAAAAAUGAGCUCCUCCACCUUGGAGGAAGGUGUUAUGGUCGUGCAUUAAAACUGAUGUCUACAUCUAAUACAUGGUGUGACCUUGGAAUUAAUUAUUAUCGCCAAGCACAACAUCUAGCAGAAACAGGCAGCAACAUGAAUGAUCUUAAGGAGUUGCUGGAGAAAUCUUUACAUUGUCUGAAAAAAGCAGUGAGACUCGACAGUAAUAAUCACUUAUACUGGAAUGCUCUUGGUGUGGUUGCAUGUUACAGUGGUAUUGGAAAUUAUGCCCUUGCUCAGCACUGUUUCAUCAAAUCAAUCCAGUCAGAACAAAUUAAUGCUGUUGCAUGGACCAACUUGGGAGUGUUAUACCUCACAAAUGAAAACAUUGAGCAAGCUCAUGAGGCUUUCAAAAUGGCUCAAUCCCUUGAUCCAUCUUAUUUAAUGUGCUGGAUUGGACAAGCUCUUAUUGCUGAGGCAGUUGGAAGUUAUGACACCAUGGAUCUCUUCAGGCACACUACAGAACUAAAUAUGCAUACUGAAGGAGCAUUAGGUUAUGCGUAUUGGGUCUGCACAACAUUGCAAGAUAAAAGCAACAGAGAAACAGAGCUGUACCAGUACAACAUCCUCCAGAUGAAUGCUAUUCCAGCAGCACAAGUUAUUUUGAAUAAAUAUGUAGAAAGAAUUCAGAAUUAUGCCCCAGCUUUCACAAUGUUGGGUUACUUAAACGAACAUCUACAACUGAAAAAGGAAGCAGCAAAUGCAUACCAAAGGGCAAUUUUGUUGUUACAGACUGCAGAAGACCAAGAUACUUACAAUGUUGCAAUAAGAAAUUACGGCAGAUUGUUAUGUUCCACUGGUGAAUAUGAUAAAGCUAUCCAGGCUUUUAAGUCAACACCCCUUGAAGUGUUAGAAGACAUCAUAGGUUUUGCAUUGGCUUUAUUCAUGAAGGGGCUUUAUAAAGAGAGCAGCAAAGCCUAUGAGAGAGCCUUGUCUAUUGUUGAAUCGGAGCAAGACAAAGCCCAUAUCUUGACAGCUCUGGCAAUAACUGAAUAUAAACAAGGAAAAACGGAUGUAGCCAAGACAUUGCUAUUUAAAUGCUCUAUCUUAAAGGAACCAACCACAGAAAGCCUUCAAGCCCUGUGUGCUCUAGGGUUGGCAAUGCAGGAUGCUACACUGUCAAAAGCAGCACUUAAUGAGUUACUGAAGCACAUCAAACACAAAGACAGUAAUUAUCAGAGGUGCCUUCUUACAUCAGCGAUUUAUGCACUCCAAGGCCGCAGUGUGGCUGUGCAAAAACAAAUAUCUAAAGCUGUUCACAGCAACCCUGGUGACCCUGCUCUUUGGUCUCUGUUGUCUCGAGUUGUUGCACAGUAUGCUCAACGAAAUGCAAAGGGAGGUGUUGUAGCAGGAAAUGUGGCUCAUAUUCUGGACUCAAAUCAUGGAAAGAAGGCAUUACUGUACACUGCGGUAAAUCAGUUGGCUAUGGGAAGCAGUUCAGCAGAAGAUGAAAAAAAUACUGCACUAAAGACCAUUCAGAAGGCAGCUCUCCUUUCUCCAGGUGAUCCUGCUAUCUGGGCUGGGCUAAUGGCAGCCUGUCACGCUGAUGAUAAACUGGCCUUAGUGAACAACACUCAGCCAAAGAGGAUAGAUUUAUACUUGGCACUGUUAUCUGCUGUUUCUGCUUCAAUUAAAGACGAAAAAUUCUUUGAAAAUUACAACCAGUCCCUUGAAAAGUGGUCUCUCUCACAAGCUGUCACUGGUCUAAUAGACACAGGAAGAAUAUCUGAAGCUGAAACUCUCUGCACAAAGAAUUUAAAAAGUAACCCUGAUCAGCCAGCCGUUAUCUUACUUUUGAGACAAGUUCAGUGUAAACCACUCCUGGAGUCACAAAAGCCACUCCCAGAUGCUGUACUUGAAGAACUACAAAAAACAGUCAUGUCCAACUCAACCUCUGUUCCAGCUUGGCAGUGGCUGGCACAUGUGUAUCAAUCCCAAGGAAUGAUGAGAGCUGCAGAGAUGUGUUACAGAAAGAGUCUACAAUUGGCAUCCCAACGGGGCAGUUGGAGUGGGAAGCUCUCAAGUCUGUUGAGACUAGCACUACUUGCAUUAAAAGUCUGUAUGGCUAACAUUUCCAAUGAUCACUGGCCAUCUUUGGUUCAAGAGGCUACAACUGAGGCCUUGAAGCUUUGCUUUUGUCCACUGGCUGUUCUUUUACAAGCUUUGUUACAAUUCAAACGCAAAAUGGGGGCAAGAGAGACACGGCGUCUUUUGGAAAGAGUGGUAUAUCAGCCUGGGUAUCCCAAAUCUAUUGCAUCAACUGCACGUUGGUACCUACUGAGACACUUAUAUGCCAAAGAUGACUAUGAGCUUAUUGACGUGCUGGUAAACAAUGCCAAAACUCAUGGAGAUACAAGAGCAUUGGAACUGAAUCAGAGAUUGUCCUCACAAUAACAUUGGAUUAUUUUAUAGUAAGGAAGCAAAGAAAAAGCUGUAAGAAUGAAGCAAUGAAUCAAGACUUCUACCCAAAGCAACAUUUUUUUAAACUAUAUUUAUUCCUUUUCUAAAGGAAUCUAGAGAAGUUGAAGUUUUUAAGUUAGGAAUGCAAUUUUCUGUUAACUCCAAACCUGAUUUUAAUCUGAAAAAAAAAAAAUUUAAUUUGGGAAAACCAGAAUGAAAGGAAAACCAUUAUUGCCUUGGUUGCUUAACAUUAUUUGUAAACCAUUAUUUUCUGCAUCUUGCAUGGUGCACAAUAGAAUAUCUUUUACUGUAAUCCCUUACAAUAAAGCCUUAAUAGCCAUUUUCUAUGUAAUAUGCAAAAGUAGAUUAGCACAAUGCACAAUUUUCUUUUGUUAAAAAUCAAAUUCAAAGAUUUAAUUCUUGCUAUGAAUUCUAAAGUUCGGCAAACCAAUUCAUCAUAAAAUCCAAAUAAUCUUGUAACCUAUUUAUCUAGUGAUUCAUCUCCAAUUCUGUUGAAAAAGCAUAAUAUAAAUGUUGAUGAGACUAGACUCUAAUGGAUAUGUUUAUAUAAUUCCAAACACUCAGGUGUGUGAAUGCAUUUAAAAACAUUAAUGGAAAAUAAUGCUGAUAAUAUUUAAUUGAUCAUGCAAUUCCUUCAAUUAUGAUGGAAAGACUUGAACUUUCUGAAAUAAAACAAAAAUACAGCA